AUCCGGAGGGGACGGCCCAGCCAGGCUGGGGUCCGCGCGGGGCCUCCCGAGAGGCGGCAAGGGGCGCUGGGAAGGCGCAAGCCCGCGCCGGCUCCCUGCGGAUGCCCGGGUCGGAGAGGGGCGCCCGGGAGGGGCGGGUCUACUGGCACGUGGAGGGGCCGGCCCGGGUUCGCGGUUCCCCGUGCCCAGGCAGGAGGGGCUGCAGACGCCUGAGCUCCGUAGGGGUUGGGGCUGGGGGCUGCGGAGCUGUCUACAUCGGACUCCUCCGGGUCAGCCCGUUAGGAGCCGCCUCCCCUCUGCCCCUCCGAAGAGACGAGCGGCCCAGACAGGCCUGGGAAGGCCCCUCUGCCCCGUCAGGGGUGAAAAGCAAAGCUGGAAGGAUUCGGAGAGGGUUGGGGCCGUCUUCCUCAUCCUUCCUUUUCUCGGGGCUCCCGUGGCGACGUCAUGGCAAAUUCCCAAACUGGACGGAUCCGGCUCGGGUUACGUCCAGCAGGGCCGAGCCGGCCCAGGCCGGCCCCGGGGUCCUCGGUGCCGGCUGGAGGGGCUGGGCACCUCUGGGGCGGGGUUCUGCUCCACCUGCCCUCGGCGCGGACUGUGCCCUCGGCGGGCACGCGGACCGGCGGGGUAGGGCUAGGGCCCGGCUUCUCUGGGCCAAGGAUCAAGGUCCCUGCCUGGGUUAGGCCCCCACGCAUUCCAGUCUUCGGAACCCGGCCUCUGAAGAGGGCGCAGUAGGGCCCCAGCGGAGCGCGAGAACCCGCUCUACAGCCUAUUGCUUCCCCGCCCUGGGCAGAGCCACCUGGACAUGAGACCCGCCCUCAAUGCCGAAGCCUCUCGGAAGCAAUCUUUCGGGACGGAAGUUAAGUAGCCCCGAGCGGGAGGCUGUGGCGGAAGUGGUCGCGUUACCGCUUGUUUGUGCGCAUGCGCCACUCUCGUCUGGCCGCCGCGCUUUCAGGAGGUGCUUUUGGUUCUCUCCGGUCUUGUCCACGCUAGGGGGUGCACGUACUCCCAACUGUGGUCGCGCUCUCACCCCUUCUGCUGCUCUCGUGGCCCCCUCGCGAUGGCGGGCAUCCUGUUUGAGGAUAUUUUCGAUGUGAAGGAUAUUGACCCGGAGGGCAAGAAGUUUGACCGAGUGUCUCGACUGCAUUGUGAGAGUGAAUCUUUCAAGAUGGAUCUAAUCUUAGAUGUAAACAUUCAAAUUUACCCUGUAGACUUGGGUGACAAGUUUCGGUUGGUCAUAGCUAGUACCUUGUAUGAAGAUGGUACCCUGGAUGAUGGUGAAUACAACCCCACUGAUGAUAGGCCUUCCAGGGCUGACCAGUUUGAGUAUGUAAUGUAUGGAAAAGUGUACAGGAUUGAGGGAGAUGAAACUUCUACUGAAGCAGCAACACGCCUGCUGAGAUUGAGAGCUGCUGAGUGGCAGUGCUCCAGAAUCACGGGAUGGGGCCUUCUGUUUCAGCUCUGCGUACGUGUCCUAUGGGGGCCUGCUCAUGAGGCUGCAGGGGGAUGCCAACAACCUGCAUGGAUUCGAGGUGGACUCCAGAGUUUAUCUCCUGAUGAAGAAGCUAGCCUUCUGAACCUCGCCUGAAGCCAGCCUCUCUGCCAAGUCACUCAGGUCAUGGGCAUUGUUCAAGCCUGAGUGGCAGCCGCUCUUGCUCACCUGUUGAGGAAGGGCUGGCUCACUGUCCACCGUGGCGGCAUCUUUAACUGGCCUCCACUCAAUGGGAAACUGACUCGCCUGUGAAAGACACAGUGGGAGAGCUGAAAAUGAAUCAGAAGCUUUAUGUAUAUGAUUUUUAAAUUAAACUUUACUUUUUCAGACUGCCCCUCCCCUUUUUGUAAAAAGUCCAUUUACUGUAAAAUCGUUUUUUCCA